GCUUUAUGAGCCUGCAGGCAAAGAGUGAUCAUUUGCCUCUCAAGCAGCCUCUGGUCAUCUAUCUGCCUUUGAGCCAUCAAGAUGCCGAUGUCUUCUCUUCCAGCAGCUAUUUUGUCUCACAUGACAGCUAUUAACAAUGUGCCUCCUCCUCCACUUCACAGUAUACCAAACUUGAAAAAGUCUAAGCACAUUAAUUAUGGCCAGUUGAAUGCAUUAUGCCACAUUAGAGGACAACACAGCCGGAGUAUGAGCAAUAUCUUAUCAGCUCACGAUACAUUUAUGAAGCAAUAUCCUAAAGUAUUCCUGCACCAAAAACCCAGACUUCCUAAACUUUUCAAACAGGAGGAACAAAGGGAACUCAAUGAAGGCAAAGAGGAAAGUCAACAUCAACAACCUGAUGAUUCUAACAAUAUAGCUGUCCAUGUUCAGAGAGCACAUGGUGGCCAUAUUUUAUAUAGACCAAAAAGAGCCACAGAGAAAUUUGAAGAAUUCCUAGCUAUCUUAAAGAAAUUGCCCAUUCACAGGACGCCAUAUGAACACAAAACUGUGUGGAAGUUCCUGAAAACAAUUCCAGAUUUAACCUUUCAGCUAAAUGAUAAGCAUCUGAAAACACUUAGUAAGACUGUCUUUUCCGAAACCUGGUUGAAAGGCAGCACAGUGGUUGCAAAUGAUGGAUUUUAUGUAAUACUGAAAGGCCUAGCUCGACCUCAAACAAACGUGUAUAAAAAUCUGAUUGAAGGAAGUGAUUCACCAGACUCGUUCAUAUCUCAGAGUUUCCACAGCUUCAUUUGGAGUGAAGAAUUCAAAAACUCUACACUUGCUGAGAUGUACCUACCUUCAUAUGACUCAAUGCUUAGCAAAUGGAGUACCUUUGGGACUCUGGAAGUUAUGCCUCAGAAUGAAUCGGAAACACAGAUGUUCUCGGUGGUGACAGAAGACGAUUGUGAAAUUCUUAAAAUCCCAGCAAAGGGAUAUGCAAAGAUAAAGGAGGAAAAAAUAAAACUUGAAAAUAUGCAAAAGUUGAAAUUAAUCCGUAUGUGUCCUUAUUAUGAGGAAUGGCCUACUUUAUCCAUAUAUGAGCUAAUUGCACUCCUUAAAUGGAAAAAAUUUCCUCCAGGUCAUGUGAUAGUGGAAAGUGGAAAUAUAAUUUCUUUUGUGGGUUAUAUUAACUCUGGAUGCUGUAACAUUUAUAGAAGUAUUAUAGGAUUUGUGAAACUACGAUCAAAUAAAGUGAAAAGAUCUCAAAAACUUGUUUAUAUGGGGAAACUUAAGGAGAAGGAGUCCUUUGGUGAGAUUAGCGUCCUUCUUCAAGUUCCUUUCACGUGCACAAUCAUUACCAAAAAAGAAGUUGAGAUGGCAAUCAUUGAAGAUAAGGACCUAUUUGUGGCCUAGAUCUAGAAACAACCUCAGUGAACAUUAAUUAAGAAAGUAUUGACUAAAUAAUGGAAUAAUUGCAUUCUGGAAUACUAUCAAACUACCAGCAAUGAAUUUGGUCUAUUGUGACUACAUAUCCUGGAUUCCCCAGGAAAGUCCCACUUUCGAAUUGCCUUUCAAACACAGUUUUUAUUAGCAGUCUUUCUUGGUUUGGAUACUAAAAUAAAUAUAGUUAUCAUUGCUUGAUUUA